GAAGCCCGGUCUCCGGGUAAGAUGGCAGCGGACGGACAGUGCUCGCUCCCCGCUUCAUGGCGGCCGGUGACCCUCACCCACGUCGAAUAUCCUGCAGGUGAUCUCUCUGGCCACCUCCUUGCCUACCUGAGCCUCAGCCCUGUAUUUGUCAUCGUCGGUUUCGUGACCCUCAUCAUAUUUAAGCGGGAGCUGCACACGAUCUCCUUCCUUGGGGGCCUGGCACUGAACGAGGGGGUCAACUGGCUGAUCAAAAACGUCAUCCAGGAGCCACGGCCCUGUGGAGGCCCCCACACAGCAGUGGGCACCAAGUACGGGAUGCCCUCCAGCCAUUCCCAGUUUAUGUGGUUCUUCUCCGUCUAUUCCUUCCUUUUCCUGUAUUUAAGAAUGCACCAAACAAACAACGCCAGGUUCCUGGACUUGCUGUGGAGGCACGUGCUCUCCCUGGGACUCCUCGCUGUGGCCUUCCUAGUCUCCUACAGCAGGGUCUACCUGCUGUACCACACCUGGAGCCAGGUGCUCUAUGGAGGCAUCGCUGGAGGCCUCAUGGCCAUCGCCUGGUUCAUCUUCACCCAGGAGGUCCUCACCCCGCUGUUCCCCAGGAUAGCAGCCUGGCCUGUCUCCGAGUUCUUCCUAAUCCGAGACACAAGCCUCAUUCCCAACGUACUCUGGUUUGAGUACACGGUAACCCGGGCAGAAGCCAGGAACAGACAACGCAAGCUGGGGACGAAACUGCAGUGACCAGUGGGUGUGGCUGGGUCCAGCCUCCAGAUCUGGCCCGCACGAUGCCUUGCAGGAUGGACAGGAUGACAGACAGGGACGAAGCAGAGACCUCUACAGACCCAAGUCACCAAGUGGAGCCUUUUUUUUUCUUAUUUUAAUUUUAAUGAACAAGGUGGACCAAAGGGCUGAACCAGCCCCUCAACCAGGACCCUGGGGGGCCUGCUGCCUGGGGGCCGUGGCCAGAGACCCUCGCUGUGCUGCUGCCAGCCCCUGGCUGGGCAGAAAGUGCCCUCGGCAUGGGCACCUGGGUGUGGGGUGGAGGAGGAGGGCUCGCGCCUCUGGUCUCGGGGCCAGGAAUUCCAGGUGGCGUGAGAAGUACACACUAUUUAUUUUUUGGUUUUGUCAGAGGCAGGCAGGAUUUUGGAGCUGGAAGAAUCUGCUCUCCGGUGGCUGCCCUGUGAACAGAGGGCUCCCGGUCAGCUUCCCAGGCCCUUCGCCCUAUGCCCAGAGGGCAGACUGCCUCUCCCUGGGCCGGGGUGGCCUGGGUGCCAGGAGGAGGGGAGCAUACCCCACACCCUCCCUGCCACCGUUGCCGUUCCAGAACCUCGGUCAGUGUUUCCCUGUCUGGGGGCAGGGCCCAGAGCGAGCACGCGUCUGGCGGCUGCUGUCGUUGUGUUCUACCCCGUACUGACCCAACACCACAAGGGCUUUCUCUGGUCCCCUGUCCCUAAGACAAUAAUCGCUUUCUGACAAAGGAGCCUGCACAUUUGGGUGAGCAGACCCAAGCUGUUUACAGCUCUUUCUUGUCCUGCCAUCCAGUAGCAGUUAGUCUUCAUCCCCACGUGAACAAAAUGGGAAGGAGCCGUGAGGAGAGGAGUGAGGCAACAGGCACCCGAAGUCCCUCGUCCUUCCCUCUGUGUGCUCUGAAUAUGUCCUUGUCCUUCCUGACCCAUCUCUGACCAGCUGGGAACCUGCUUGGGGUCCCCCUCAAACCUGUGUCUGGGGUGUGGGCUCACAGAUCCCUAUCAGCCUGGUUCGUGGGAGGGCUCUUCCUAAAGGGACCCCCAUCUCUAAGUCACUCUGAAAGGGAGUUGUGGAGAGGAGACGCCUCCAGACUCUCAGAAGUUUUGAGGACUGAACUGGGUCACUCGGGAUCUGUGUUCGAAUCCUCCCCACCCCUUUCUUUGUGGAGUUUCCUAACCUGCUGCUGAAGCACAAUGUUUUGGUGCUUUCUUUUCUCAUUUGUUAAAGGCAGUGUCCAAAAGCCAUUCCAGAUGCCAAGACCAGGGGCUUAUUUCUAGGGAAGGUAGGUCGGUUUCCAUGUUUCCCUCCCGUUAUUUUUAUUUUUUACUUUUUGCCUGAGACAAGCCGAGUAUGAGGUGGUUUGAUUUAAGAAAAAUCAAUGAAAUUGUUUACUACUGUUUUAAAAUAAAACCGUAAACUCUGGCA